GCUUCACACCUUUCCCGCCCUUAAGUAUGUGUACGUUGGGUGCAGAACCGUUUGGUUUUCCCGAGGGGUAGGCAGAAUUUCCAACCCCACGAGCUGCUCCCUCUUUCCGCAAACCUCCUAACCCCGGGGUUUUUCCAUAAAUGUGUUUACUUCGUCCACGCCAGCCUGCGAAGUUCCAAAAUGGAGUCUGGGCCACGCCGGCGUUCUGGGCACGACUACGGUCUCUUGAAAAGGUAGGGAAGAGUCGGCGAGCUCCAGCUUUGGGGGAUGCCGCGUGGCCCGGCCGCGCCUAGGCCGCCUGCUGGCCCUGCCGCCUCGAUGGGCAGGUGCGCGCCGAACGCGGGGAGCGGCCCGGAGGCUGAGCGCAGCGCAGCACCGUCCGCGGGCCCUCCUGGGCCACCUCUGCGCCCACUGGGGGCUGACCCUUGUGUUUCUCCAGGCUCAGACCCAGCCAGCCCCUCGUCCCGGCCGGCGUCUAGGGCGCAGGCAUUGCGGGGCCCACCCAAGAGCAGGUCACCCGCCAGGCUCGCCGCCCGCCCCCAGCAGCCCUCGGCGCAGAAAGGCCACGCGGCCCACGGGCGAGUUGUGGGUUUCGGGUGUGCGGAGAGGGAAGUCCCGGAGUCUGCAGUGGCCCGGCUGUGCCCCCGAGGCUGUCUCCGCGGAGCCGUUCCAUUCCUGCCGCGGCCCCGGGGACCUGAGCUGCUGGCUGGCUCUGAAAUUUCCGCUGACCCGGUCAUCUGCUGUCCUCGCGGCUCUGGACUUGCGACACCAAGGACGCUCUCAGGGAAAUGGCUAACUGACGAGGGGCGCGCGAGCAGCGGCUGCCUGAACCCCAACCGCUGCAAGUUUACGCCCCGGGAGGCCGGGAUGAAGGCCAGGGACAGGAAACGCGGAGGAGGAGGUGGAGGAGGAGGGGGCGCGCAGCGCAGGCCCCUGCCCCCCGGCCCACCCAGGAGGCUCUGCCAGCUAAGCAGCGAGCAGGUGUCAGACACAGACUUCCCUGGAGUUGACUCUCAGCCUCUCCCACUCGGACCGCGCGCCUCUCCCACUCGGACUCGGAUCCUCGAAACUUUUAAUCUUUAAAGAAUACAAUGUGAAAACCUUAUCUUUUUCCAGGGAUCCCAGCCACUACCUCCGGGGACUCGCCUCCCUUCUCCUCAGCCUUCCACUGCCUCUGCGGGGCGGGGACCUUUUGCAUUUGAACUUCCCGCACUGUUGGCCGUUUUUCGCCAGAGCCUGGAGGAGUAGGGAGCUUGGCUCUGCUCAGGGUGCGUGCACCCUGGCCCUGGAGUAGCAAGGACGCCUGGGGAACCCAGAGGAGGAUUGCGUGUACUAGGCCGAGUCGAGGGUGCGGAGACAAGGGCAAAAGGCUAAGAAUUUUAUCUUUUAAAACAGCGCGUCAGCGCCCGUGCUCUCAGCAGGGCUGAGGUGGGAAAGCGCAGCCGCGGGCUGCAGUCCGCAGCCGGCGGGAAGGGCCGCAGCGCCCCCUGGAGGCACCGGCCGAGCUCUGCGUGGCGCGGGCUGAGGGGGCGGCCACACCGGUGGUGGGCUCCGCUGCGUGAGGGCUUGGCCAACAGCUGCCCCGCCGGCCCAGCGGCUCCCUGUACCUGGGCCCGAGCCCCUUUGCUGCAGAGAAAGAGUCGCGUGUGCGGUAGGGGUCCUGUGGAGAGGGCCUGGGCCUAUUCUCAGGGCCAAUAAGCUUCUCCACACCCACCGUCGGGUCCUUUGUGGGAGCCCCACAUGGUGUCCCCCACCCCAGAGCCUUUUCUCCUGGUGGGUUUCUGAGACGGAUUUUUCGGACCCACGACGCCACUCCGGGCUGCCCUGACUUCCCCAGAGGAGGAGAAAGAUACCAGUUCUGACCCCAGCGCAGGGAGUUCGCAGGCGGUCGCGUGCGGGGCGGCGCAGAUUCCAAGGCCGGGGACCUUGUCCGGGCGGGAGAUGCAGAGGGGUUUCCCAGGGGACCGCGUGCAGACAGGCUGCCCCACUCCCACGGAUGGCGCGGGGGCCUUCCCGCGUCUGCGGGAGCUGAGGGUCGUUCCUCACUGCAGGAACCCCGCCACCCGGAAUCGGGCCGGGCCAGCCAGCCGCAGGCACCCUUCCGGCCACCAGCCUGCGAGGCACUGAGUCACAGGGAAGGGGAGCUCAGUGGGAAGGCCGAGCACGGGGUCUCAGGGCAAGUUGCGUGGCCGUGGCCGUGGUGGUCUAGCCUGGGGACAGAAACCUCCUUGAGCCCAGGUCCAGCCCGGGUUUGGAUUUCCCAGCUGAGGCCCUCGGCUGCCGCAGCGGCGGAGCCCAGAGCCGGCGCAAGGCCACCCAGGCCACCGUCAGCCCCUCGCUAGUCGCAAGAUGCCUCCGCGACCCUGGAGCGUGAGGAUGGUCCCGGGGGAGGAGCGGGCGGAAGGGCGCACCGGCUCCUGCACAAGCUGGAUACGGCUCGGGCUCCGCGGUCUCCAGGCCCGCGCCGCACGCCGAGGGGGUAGGAGCGGGCUCCCGGGGCGGCGCGCGGGCACAGAGCGUGCUUUCGCCUUCCGGUGACUCCAGGGAAGGGGAUCUCCUGCAGUUUGCCUCGUCGGAGAGAGCCAGGCUAACGCCCAUGAUCCCGCGUCCAAGGCUGCUUCGAAUUCAUGGUGCUUUUCGAACCAAGCGCUUCAGUGUCCGUGACAAGGAAGACCAGGUUUACCGAUGACAUCGCAGUGAAGGACAGGCCCCAGACACAUCCGGGGAGAGGGGGGCUCUCCGCACCGGGCCCCUCUGGGAAGGCCCCAACCGCCCAGGGCGGGACUGGCCCGGCUGUCGUGCUCAACGUGGGUAGACGAUGGAUGACAGAAAAGAACAUCCUCGGAAAAGACUAGGGCACGGUCUGCAAACCUAUAUUUUUAUUAGGCUUUCAUAUUGUGUGUGUUUUUCAACGCACUUGCCAACGCUUAAACUUUGGGAAAAUUCAAACGGAAAUCUUGAUUUCCGAUGACCUCCGUUCCUACGCGGCAGUGAGUUGGCUGGAGCUGAGCAGCGCUACCCUCCCGUCUCCAGACUUGUUUUUAAAAGGCCGGCUGAAGAUUGCCUUGGACGUUCCAUUUCUCACUGCAGAUUUCGUUUCCCUGGGACGCUGGGAUAGGUCCGAGUUACCCUCUAGAGCAGCGGUUCUUAAAGUGUGGUCCAACAGCAUUCGCAUCAUCUGGAACUUGUUAGAAAUGCAAACUCUCUGGCCUCACCUACUAAGUCAGAAACUGGGAGUGGGGCCUGGCAAUCUGUGUUUGAGCAAGCCCUCCAGGUGAUUCUGAUGCAUGGUAAAGUUUGAGAACCACUAACCUAGAUCAGAUUGACAUUGGGGUCCAUCGCGGGCGGGCGCGAUUUAUCUUUCCCGCGCGUGCUCUCUCUCCUCCUCCGUCCCUACCUCUUCCUUCUUCCUUCACUCGAGAGAAUGCACGCAUAAACGCAUCUGCUUUAGGCAGCUUAUUCAUUCAUUCACUCGCUCACUUAUUUCUCAUUCAUCAGACUUUCCAAAGGCACCUUCAAGUACUUGGAAACGAGCUUAGGAUACCUAGGGGAACAAGGCUGUACCCCUCCCCGCAAGGAGUCGGCAUAAGAUGGUGGGGAGAGCAAUGGAGAAAAAGUGCGGGUGCCUUCUUUCACGGCCAGUUGUUGUUAAUUAGUAUUAUCUAAUACUAGAUCUGACUGAUUUCCGGAAAUGUCGCACCUCAUUUUACAGUUUCUAACUAUUUGUAACACUUGCCUGCCUUCCUUGUCCGUGCCGAUGUCAUUCUUUUAUUUUCAUCACAUUUUAGGGAUUCUGUGUGUCUACUGCACACCUUCCACACACAUCUUGACACACAUUGCCCACACCUUGCCAACCCUCCCUGCAGUAGGUCAGAGUGCAUGACACUGGGGGUGAGGGAGUGUCAAAAUCCGAGGGACCACGGGUGGGCCAGGGCUCAGAGUCUCUGUGCCCCUGGAUUACCCUGAGGCUGGGCAGGAGGGUCUGAGGACAGCUGGAACUGACUCACAUGUUCCCCUCACCCACUUGGUGCACACUGGCUCCCACCCUGCUUCCUGCUGCCUCAAUCUGCCUAGCUCUCCACCUUCAAGUGCAUCCAGCAUUGGCGUCCUGAUUUGUCACCUUAAGAUGGAAUCAAGUCCCUUUGCUUUUCUUGAGGGAGUAUAAAAUAGUCUCCCUUCUCCCCCAACUAAAAAUCUGAAUGACACUGGCACUUUCUAGUCUUCUUAUGCCAAGUCAACUUCCCUUAUGAUUGUUCACUUUGCACUUUCUCUCUAGGACCUUCACUUGAACUUCUCUCCUCGGCCAAAGAGCUGCCUCCACUGGACCAUUUGCUUCCCUCCAGGAUUUUCUAGUUUUGGGCAGUGAACAAUAGAAGGCACUUUGCCUCCCCAAAAUCCCGUCUAACUGGAAGCCUCUUGUCAUCAUCUAUUUUCAAGUUUUUUUAGUUUUUUUUUUUAAGCUUUAAUUUUAGUGAGUCAGUGCAGGGAAGCCACUGAAAACGCAUAUAAACAAAAAUGAAUUUUCAUACUGACCAUAGUCAUAAAUUGUACAAAAGUAUUCAUCAUCUCCACUUUGACAAAGGGUUGCUAUUUUCAAAUGACCUUUUCUUAUGGGGAUUCUCAAAAUAUAAGAUGUUACAGUGGUCAGGAAUGUGGUAAUCUCUUUACUACCAGUGAUUCUAUUUCUUAACAGAAUUUUGCUUCCCAGUGCAGAUGGUUUGAUAUAGUAACAUUCAAAGCAGCCAGCCCUUAGGAAAUGCCAAGGCCAAUAUUUGAAUGCAGAUACAAGUUUUAACAAAGGAAAAUGUAGUAUAUCCUUGUAGCUGUUUGCCUGUGAAUAUUCCCCUGGAGGGCUAAUACACUAUUCUUGAAUCUAAUCCAAGUCAAGCCAACUCUAAAAAUCCUGUGAAGUACCGACUAAUAAGGCACAUACAAUUCCUUUUCAACAGUUUUCUUGAGUGUCUACUAUGUACCAGUGUGAAGAAACAAGAAGGCAGAGGCCUGCCAAGGACGGGGAACAGCCUCCACAAAAUUUUCAGGGACAAAAACGGAAUCUUUGUCUUCAUGCUUCUCUGCUUUCUUCAAAUGGACUCUCUGAACCUGCAAACCUCCAUGAACUCAAGAAGGCCUGACAACUCUUUCAGGGUACAAUGACUGGUUUUAGUGCUAUGGUUUUUCUUUUCUUUCCUUUUUAAUAUCAUGAAUCUAAACAAAUUCCACAGGGGGAAAAAAAUAAAAAGAACUGGCUGGCUCAACGUAAAACUAUUGAUAUGGUUCCAAAUUCUCUCCCAUCAUUGUCAACGCGCGCGCGCGCGCGCGCGCGCACACACACACACACACACACACACACGUUUUUGCAAAACUGUAACCUGCAUAUACACAGAGUUUUAUGUUCUGGUUUUUCACUUCACUUUAUUCCAUAUACACAUUUCCAUGACUUGGAGGGUACCCCAGACUUCAACACUUUUAAUAGCUAAAGGGUAUUCCAUCUUAUUUAUAUCUCUGGUUGAGUGACCAUUCACCCUUGUACUGUGGGCUUCUGGGUUGUUCUAGCCUAGGGAGACUCCGUCGUUCUGUGCUUAAGGACAUGCCCGUGGGGUUUCUCAGGCCAUGUUCACAAGUAGUGCUAGGGUUUAGGUUUGUUUGUUUGUUUUCAUGAUUUCUUCUGUCACAGUUUUCAUUUUAUGUUUGCAUGAGGUUAUUUCUGGAUUUGGUUGCUUUAAAAAAAUAUCAUAUUCAUCUUUGCCAACUAUCAAUGCAUUUGUUCUGAAAUGCAAUCAAGGCCUACUCUAAAAAGCAAACAAUACAAGUGUUGCCACCUGUUGAUGGAAAUUUUAUUACUCUUGUUUCACUGGAGCUCUGAUGAAGAACAGCGUGAAAGGAAAAAAGAAACUUUAUUAUAACUCCCACAAACUCAAUCCCCAGACUUAUUAACAUAAUAUUUGCAUUAUUACUGUUCUUUUUUUAUUUCAUACCUUCUUCUAACAUGGGUCAUUGACUGUAAGCAAGUAUACAUUUUGCUUCAUUACAAUUUGCUUUAGAUAUAUUUAAAACCUUUCCAUUUGAUCAAGGCUCCACAUUUCUUUUUAAUUUAAAAGUUUCAAACAUCAAACAUUUUGAAACCCCAUGGAUGGUGUAUACCCUAGUGCUCUACAUGAAAUGAGGUCAGCAAACAGCCAGAGUUUGACAAUCCUCAGCGGAACCAAUUUUAACUAAUUUCAAAGAAGAAAAAAUAGUUUCCAUAUUUCAUAAAAAGGGUUUGCUAAUAAACAUAAUAGAGGAAAUAGAGGAAGUUACUUUUCUUAAAGCUUCAAGAAUGAAUGAGUAUGUGUGCAUUAAGAAAAUAAGCAAACAGCAUGUACUUUGAUAAACCAUAAUUUAUAUAAAUCAAAGGACAAGAGCCAAGAAUUACAAUAGUUUGUAACCAAUGCCUUAUAAAUACUAUAGUUUAAAUAUGCAAGUAAAUAAUAAAUUCUAAGAACAGCCCUCACUCAGCGAUCAGCAGUGCCUUGUAUAUAAUAGAAGAGCAAUAAAUAAACUUCUGAAUCCCUUUU